CCCACUCCCGCCCCCACGCCGGGCUGGUAGUGGCGUGGCUACACCGUGGCCUCAAGGAGCCAGUCCUGCCCGGAUGGGGCUCGCCGGAUCGGUUUCGGUUUUCACGCACUCCCAUUUCUGUGGCCGCUGUGCAUUCGCGGAGUGUUCUCUGCUGCUUCUGGGUCCUGACAGUCUUGAAAAGAUCCAGCUGCUGAACUGCCUUGUUAGGAACCACUGCUGUGGAACUGGUGCAGUCAUUUGGAGUAGCCAUGUUGCUCACAGCUUGAGGUGCAGCAGUCUGAACCACCCGGCGGCUGAGAAGAGGAACCAAAUGAGGAACUAUUCCAGAGUCUACUACCAUCUGUAUUUGUUCAUUGCCAGCACCAGUAAGGCCCCACAGGAUCUGCCCCAACCACCAUGCCACACCGACACUCCCAGGAACCAGGCUGCCUGUGCUGCUAUGCCGGCUGUGCCACUGCUUCCUUCCUCCUCCUCAACUGCCUCAGCUGAGGCCUUCUCCUCUCCCUGUACAACUCCCUUCCUCAACCCCAGCAUGAGAGCAGAUCAGGUGGAGACAACUACGGGAGCGGAAUGGCAGCAACGGUGGCGGAAUGUAAUGCAUGCUGAGAGUGAGAUGGCCUCAAUCUCUGCACACCUUUUCAUGUGCUUAUUUUCCAUCUGUUAUAUUUUCUUCAGUGAAAUGUUUAUGUCUUUUGCCUAUUUUUAACUAGGCUUGCUUUUACUAUUACGUGUUAAGAGUUCUUGAUAUAUUCUAGAUACUAGUUUGUUACUGGAUACGUUAUUUGUAGUAUUUUCUCCCAGUCUGUAGCUCUGUAGCUUCUGUAGAGGAAAAGUUUUUAAUUUUAUUGAGGUCUAAUAUAUCAACUUUUCCUGUUAUGAAUCAUACUUUUAGUAUCAAGUGACUUACCUGAAAUUUUUCUAAGUUUUCUUCUAAAAGAUUUAUAGUUUGAGCAUUUUACAUUUAAAUUUAUGAUCCAUUUUGUAUAAAGUAUGAGGUGUAGGUGAAGGUUAAUUUUGAGCGGAGAGGGCAAUGGAUUGUUCAGCAUCAUUUGUUGAAAAGACUAUCCUUCCCCCAUUUAAUUACUUCUGUAAUAAUUUAGGCGUAUCUGUGCAGGUCGGCUUUUGGGUUCUCUAUUCUCUUCUAUUGAGUUUCGUAUCUAUCCCUCUACCACUGCCGCACAGACUUGAUUACCAUAGCCAUAUAAAUGUCUUGAAAUUGAGUAUAAUGGUUCCUCCCACCUUAUACUUCUUUGUCAAAUUGUCUUAGCUAUUCUACCUCCGCUGACUUUACAUACACAUUUUAGAAUAAUGUUGACUACAUCUCCAAAAAAAAUCUGCCUGCGAUUUUCAUAGGAAAUGUAUUGUAAUUGCAUACCAAUUUGGGAAGGGCUGACAUUUUUACUGUGUUGAUUUUGACAAUCCACGAACAUGCAAUGUGCCUCUCCAUUCAUUUAGAUCUUUAAUUUCUUUAUCAGCAUUUUCUAAUUGUCAGCAGAUCUUAUACAUGUUUUGCUACAUUUGCAUUUACGUAUUUAUUUGAAUGAUUAUGAAUGAUAUAUUUUUUAUUUCAAUGUCUGUAUGUUCAUUGCUAGUAUAUGAAGCACAAGUGAUUUAUGUAUGUUGAUAUUGUGUCCUAUGAUUGCGUUGAAGUCACCUAUGUUGAUGGGUGCAGCACACCAACAUGGCACAUGUAUACAUAUGUAACAAACCUGCACAUUGUGCACAUGUGCCCUAAAACUUAAAGUAUAAUAAUAAUAAUAAAAAUAAAAAGAGAAUUAGCUAAGAAUUCAAAAAAACUUUUGACGAAGCAUAAUACUUUUUUUUUUAUUAUUAUUUUUUGAGACAGAGUCUCACGCCAUUCUCCUGUCUCAGCCUCCAGAGCAGCUGGGACUACAGGUGCCUGCCAUCACGGCUGGCUAUUUUUUUUUUUUUUUUUUUUUUGUAUUUUUAGUAGAGACGGGGUUUCACUGUGUUAGCCAGGAGGGUCUCGAUCUCCUGACCUCGUGAUCCACUGGACUCGGCCUCCCAAAGUGCUGGGAUUACAGGCAUGAGCCACUGUGCCCAGCUGACAGGGCAUAAUACUUUUUAUGAUUUAUUUUUUAGUUUUUUGGCUUUCCUAUUUAUAAUUCAGAAUAUAGUAUCAUCUAUUAUAGUUAUACCUAUAUUUUUCUGACAAUAUUUCCUAAUUUUUUAUUUUCCAAUUUUAUAAACAAUAUUUUCAUUUGAUUCCAGUCUAUAAACUAUUUCUACAUAACGAUUAAUAAUACCAUUUCUAUAAAUGUCAUGUGCUGUAUACGUGGCAUGGCGUAUACAGAUAGUUUUGUGUUUUAUGUUUUGUUAUAUAACCUAUAUUGAGUUAAAUUUUGUGGAGUGUGUAAGCUCUGUGUCUAGAUUCAAUUUUUUUCUUUUUUAAUAUGUGGAUGUUGAGUUGUUCUGGCACCAUUGGUUAAAAAGACUUUCCUUUCUCUGUUGAAUUGUCUUUGUUCCUUUGUCAAAGCUGAGUUGAUUAUAUUUCUGUGGGUCAAUUUCUGGGCUCUCCAUUCUGUUCCAUUGAUCUAUUUGUACUUGUUGUUUGUUUGUUUCCAAUAACACCCUGUCUUAAUUAUUGUAGCUUUGCAGUAAGUGUUAAAGUCAGGUAGUUUCAGUUCUCCAACUUUGUUAUUCUGAUUCAAUAUUGUGUUGGCUAUUCUGAGUCUUUGGUGUCUCUAUAUAAACUUUACAAUCAGCCUGUCAGUAUUCACAAAGUAACUUACUAAGAUUUUGAUUGAGAUUUUAUUGGAUCUAUAAAGUUGGGAAGAACUGACAGAUUGGCAAUAUUGAAUCUUUCUAUCCAUGAGCAUAGAAUAUCUCUUCAUUUAUUUAGUUCUUUGAUUUCAUCAGAUUUUUAUAGUUUUCCUUGUGUUGAUCUUGCAUAUAUUUCGUUAGAUUUAUAGCUAAGUAUGCCAUUUUUUGUGUGCUAAUGUAAAUGGUAUUGUGUUUUUAAUCUGAAAUUCCACUUGUUCAUUGCUAGUAUGUUGGAAAGCAAUUGAUUUGUGUAUAUUAUAUUAAACUUGUAAAUGCAAAAAAAAACAGUUGUUCUCUGGUUUUCUAGAUUCGUUGGGAUUUUUUCUACAUAAACAAUCAUGUCAUCUGCAAAUAGAGACAGUUUUAUUUCUCCCUUUCCAAUCUGUAGGUCUUUCAUUUAUUUUUCUUGCCUUAAUUCUAUGGCUAGGACUUCCAAUACUAGUUAAGAUUUUGAAGUCACAAAUUAUGAAUUAAAUUACUGUCAAACCUUGGAGAUAAUGUAGGUUCAGUUCCAGGCCACUGCAAUAAAGCAAUUGUCACAGUAAAGUGAGUAUCACAAUAAAGCCAGUCACACAAUUUUUUGGCAUGUAAUUAUGUUUACAAUAUACUGUAGUCUAUUAAGUAUGCAACAACAUUAUAUCUAAAAACUGUAUAUAUCUUAAUUAAAAAUACUUUAUUACUAAAAAAUGCCAGCAAUCGUUUGAGCUUUCAGCAGGUAGUAAUCUUUUUGCUGGUGGGAAGUCUUGCCUCGACGUUGAUGGCUGCUGACUGCUCAGGGUACUGGUGGUUGAAGGUUGGAGUGGCUGUGGUAAUGUCUUAAAAUAUGACAACAAUGAAGUGUGCCACAUCGAUGUACUCAUCCUUUCAUGAAAGAUUCCUCUGUAGCAUGUGAUGCUAUUUCAGGCAUUUUACCCACAGCAGAACUUCCUUCAAAACUGGAGACGAUCCUCUGAAACCGUGACACUGCUUUUUCAACUAAGUUUAUAUAAUAUUAUAAAUCCUUUGCUAUCAUUUCGACAAUGUUCACAGCAUCUUUACUAGGAGUAAAUUCCAUCAAAUAAAUCACUUUCUUUGCUCAUCCAUAAGAAGCAACUCCUCAUCCAUUCAAGUUUUAUCAUGAGAUUGCAGCAAUUCAGUCACAUCUUCAGGAACCACUUCUAUUUAUAUUUCUCUUGGUAUUUCACCAUAUCUGCCGUUAUAUCCUCCACUGAAGUCUUGAACUCAUCAAAAUCAUCCAUGAGAGUUGGCAUCAACUCUUUCCAAACUUCUGUUAAUGUUGAUAUUCUGACCUCCUCCCAUAAAUCAUGAAUAUUCUUUUUUUUAGAAAAAUUAUACUUUAAGUUUUAGGGUACAAGUGCACAAUGUGCAGGUUUGACACAUAGGUAUACAUGUGUCAUGUUGGUUUGCUGCACCCAUCAACUCGUCAUUUACAUAAGGUAUUUCUCCUAAUGCUAUCCGUCCCCUAGCCCCUCACCCCCCAACAGGCCCCAGUGUGUGAUGUUCCUUACCCUGUGUCCAAGUGUUCUCAUUGUUCAAUUCCCACCUAUGAGUGACAACAUGCGGUAUUUGGUUUUCUGUUUUUGUGAUAGUUUGCUGAGAACGACGGUUUCCAGCUUCAUCCAUGUCCCUGCAAAGGACAUAAACUCAUCCUUUAUUAUGGCUGCAUAGUAUUCCAUGGUGUAUAUGUGCCACAUUUCCUUAAUCCAGUCUAUCAUUGAUAAACAUUUGGGCUGGUUCCAAGUCUUUGCUAUUGUGAAUAGUGCCACAAUAUACAUACGUGUGCAUGUGUCUUUAUAGUAGCAUGAUUUAUAAUCCUUUCGGUAUAUACCCAGUAAUGGGAUUGCUGGGUCAAAUGGUAUUUCUAGUUCUAGAUCCUUGAGGAAUCACCACACUGUCUUCCACAAUGGUUGAACUAAUUUACACUCCCACCAACAGUGUAAAAGCAUUCCUAUUUCUCCACAUCCUCCCCAGCAUCUGUUGUAUCCUGACUUUUUAAUGUUCGCCAUUCUAAUUGGUGUGAGAUGGUAUCUCACUGUGGUUUUGAUUUGCAUUUCUCUGAUGACCAGUGAUGACGAGCAUUUUUUCAUGUCUGUUGGCUGCAUAAAUGUCUUCUUUUGAGACGUGUCUGUUCACAUGCUUUGCCCACUUUUUGAUGGGGUUUUUUUUUCUUGUAAAUUUGUUUAAAUUAUUUGUAGAUUCUGGAUAUUAGCCCUUUGUCAGAUGGGUAGAUUGCAAAAAUUUUCUCCCAUUCUGUAGGUUGCCUGUUCACUCUGAUGAUAGUUUCUUUUGCCAUGCAGAAGCCCUUUAGUUUAAUUAGAUCCCAUUUGUCUAUUUUGGCUUUUGUUGCCAUUGCUUUUGGUGUUUUAGUCAUGAAGUCCUUGCCUAUGCCUAUGUCCUGAAUAGUACUGCCUAGGUUUUCUUCUAGGGUUUUUAUGGUUUUAGUUCUAACAUUUAAGUCUUUAAUCCAUCUGGAAUUAAUUUUUGUAUAAGGUGUAAGGAAGGGAUCCAGUUUCAGCUUUCUACAUAUGGCUAGCCAGUUUUCCCAGCACCAUUUAUUAAAUAGGGAAUCCUUUCCCCAUUGCUUUUUUUUUUUUUUUUUGGCAGGUUUGUCAAAGAUCAGAUGGUUCUAGAUGUGUGGUGUUAUUUCUGAGGGCUCAGUUCGGUUCCAUUGGUUUAUAUAUCUGCUUUGGUACCAGCACGAUGCUGUUUUGGUUACUGUAGCCUUGUAGAAUAGUUUGAAGUCAGGUAGCGUGAUGCCUCCAGCUUUGUUCUUUUUGCUUAGGAUUGUCUUGGCAAUGCAGGCUCUUUUUUGGUUCCAUAUGAACUUUAAAGCAGUUUUUUCCAAUUCUGUGAAGGAAGUCAUUGGUAGUCUGAUGGGGAUGGCAUUGAAUCUAUAAAUUACCUUGGGCAGUAUGGCCAUUUUCACUAUAUUGAUUCUUCCUACCCAUGAGCAUGGAAUGUUAUUCCAUUUGUUUGUUCCUCUUUUAUUUCGUUGAGCAGUGGUUUUUAGUUGUUCUUGAAGAGGUCCUUCACAUCCCUUGUAAGCUGGAUUCCUAGGUAUUUUAUUCUCUUUGUAGCAAUUUUGAAUGGGAAUUCACUCAUGAUUUGGCUCUCUGUUUGUUUGUUAUUGGUGUAUAGGAAUCCGUGUGAUUUCUGCACAUUGAUUUUGCAUCCUGAGACUUUGCUGAAGUUGCUUAUCAGCUUAAGGAGCAUUCCCUUUGAAAACCAGCACAAGACACGGAUGCCCUCUCUCACCACUCCCAUUCAACAUAGUGUUGGAAGUUCUGGCCAGGGCAAUCAGGCAAGAGAAAGAAAUAAAGGAUAUUCAAUUAGGAAAAGAGGAAGUCAAAUUGUCCCUGUUUGCACAUGACAUGAUU